ACUGGAGUUUAGGGCUGCAUUCAGACGGGCUGCAUUCAGACAGCCUGCGAGCCGCCAGGUGAUCCACGGGCUGGGCUUCGCUUCUGCUGUCCCCUGCGAUCCAACUCCCCAAUGGCAGCGGCCGCCAGCCCCGCGUUCCUUCUACGCCUCCCGCUUCUGCUCCUGCUGUCCAGCUGGUGCAGGACCGGGCUGGCCGACCCUCACUCUCUUUGCUAUGACAUCACCGUCAUCCCUAAGUUCAGACCUGGACCACGGUGGUGUGCGGUUCAAGGCCAGGUGGAUGAAAAGACUUUUCUUCACUAUGACUGUGGCAGCAAGACAGUCACACCCGUCAGUCCCCUGGGGAAGAAACUAAAUGUCACAACGGCCUGGAAAGCACAGAACCCAGUACUGAGAGAGGUGGUGGACAUACUUACAGAGCAACUGCUUGACAUUCAGCUGGAGAAUUACAUACCCAAGGAACCCCUCACCCUGCAGGCCAGGAUGUCUUGUGAGCAGAAAGCCGAAGGACACGGCAGUGGAUCUUGGCAGCUCAGUUUCGAUGGACAGAUCUUCCUCCUCUUUGACUCAGAAAACAGAAUGUGGACAACGGUUCAUCCUGGAGCCAGAAAGAUGAAAGAAAAGUGGGAGAAUGACAAGGAUAUGACCAUGUCCUUCCAUUACAUCUCAAUGGGAGACUGCACAGGAUGGCUUGAGGACUUCUUGAUGGGCAUGGACAGCACCCUGGAGCCAAGUGCAGGAGCACCACCCACCAUGUCCUCAGGCACAGCCCAACCCAGGGCCACGGCCACCACCCUCAUCCUUUGCUGCCUCCUCAUCAUGUGUCUCCUCAUAUGCUCCAGGCACAGUCUGACCCAAAGCCAUGGCCACCACCCUCAGUCCCUGCAGCCUCCUCCUCAUCCUCCCCUGCUUCAUCCUACCUGGCUGCUGAGGAGAGUCCUUUGGAGUGACAGGUAUGGGGGCAGAAUUGGGAGUGGAGCAAAGGGCAGGUGGGUGAGGAGGGAGGACAGGGAUGGAGAAUUCCCAGAGUCCCACUCCCUAUGGCUGGGACCUUCUCAUCCUAACAUGAGACAGGUGAAUGAGACCUUGUGUUGCUUGUUGGAAAUGACCUGGGCAGCUCUGCCCUGAGUUCUGAUGGAUUCUCACCAUCAAAGGCCAGAGGGAAAGGCGCAGUGGUGCCAUACCAAGGCUCAGGGUCUGUUGAGCUUGAGAGGGUUUAGCAAGUUCAGGCCUGAUUCAGAGCAGGUUUCUGUUCAGGAAGGGUGUGUGGCCUGCAGGCAGCAGGAAUUCAGACAUGGGCAGUCCUCUUAAUUGGGUUAGGUGCAUCAGGGUAGCUUUACAUGAGGUAUGACAAGGGAAGGGGGAUUCCAUCUCUGAGGCUAAGAGAGAGAUAUGUGUGGGCGGCAAGCCACCCAGGUGCCAAGGCAAGAGACUGAAGGCACAAGCUGUUCCAGUAUAAUAAAGAAAAUACUUAAAAUAAGAAUAGUUGUAUUAGACGUAGAAUACAGACAUGAUUAUCUAUGAAUAUUAUCAAUCAUUAGUCUGUAGUGUUACUCUUUUUUCCAAUGUUAUAAUAAUCUCUGUUCCACAAUUAUAACCCAGGAAAAACCAGGCCAUGCAGAGACAGGAGCUGAAGGGACACGGUGAGAAGUGACCAGAAGACAAGAGUGUGAGCCCUCUGUCAUGCCCAGACAGGGCCAGUAGUGGGCUCCUCAGUCUAGCAGUAGCGCCAGUGCCUGGGAAGGCACUUGUUACUUAGCAGACCGGGAAAAGGAGUUUCCCUUUCCCCGGGGGAGUUAGAGAAGACUCUGCUCCACCACCUCUUGUGGAAGGCCUGACAUCAGUCAAGCCUGCCCGCAGCCAUCCGGAGGCCUAAACGUCUCCCUGUGAUGCUGUGCUUCAGGGUCACGCUCCUGGUCCACUUUCAUGUUCCGCCCUGUACACCUGGCUCCGCCUUCUAGAUAGCGGUAGCAGAAUUAGUGAAAGUAUUGAAGUCCGAGAAAUACAUAGAAGAAACAAUGACGUAAGCUGUCCUCUCUCUCUCCGCCUCAGCUACCAAAUAGCGAAGCGCCCCUUGUCUGGUGGACACGUGACUCGCGUGACUUUACCUAUCAUUGGAGACGACUCACACUCCUUACCCUGCCCUCUUGCCUUGUAUACAAUAAAUAACGGCGCAGCCAGGUAUUCGGAGCCACUACAGGUCUCCAUAUCUUGAUGGUUCCCUGGGCCCAGCUGUCUUUUCUUCCGUC